CUUACCUUCCAGGAUCAGAAGUACUGAGGAGCAGAGCCAAUCUUCUCUGUUUGGUGAUAGAUAUAUGUAGAUGGGUUUAUAUGACUUUGAGUUUAGUUUGUAAAAUCUAGAUGUCCCUGCCCUAGACAGGGGACAAUGAUAUUUAGUUUGGGUUAUUUUGUACCCUGUGGAGAACAGAGUUUAGUGAAAGGGAAGCAUUUCUUUGAAAUGUGGUUCUAUGUGUUCAGUCCUAUUUCCAAAACGCAGGAGGGAAUGGAAGGGAAAACGUCCUGGCCCAAGAAUACCUGUAAAACUCAAUUGCUGUUGUAAAUUCAUCUGCCGAAAACAGUGCCUGUAACCUGUGUGGAGAAACAAUACUUUGGGUUUCUGUACAGGUUUUUCAUGAGUCCAGGAUUCAUGGGCAGCCAGUGAUUAGGAAUCCUCAAACACUCACACUCUAGAGUGUGAAUUCAAGAGAGGUGAAUUCCAAAUUCAGAAUCUGGGAGUAGAGAGGUGCUGAAGCCCAUCAUCAUGAGUGCUUGUGACCUGGGCACACACACCAUCAUACACACACCUCCUACAUAGACCCCUCUUCUACCGGGACAGGGAGCCAAAUUGAUUAGUGUCUAUCACUGCAGGAAAUAGUGGCUUGGAAAUGGACAUGCUCCAGGACCUUGAGUCCCUGCAGUUUGAGUAUGGGGUUCCAGAGGAAGAUCGUAUCUGGCUGUAUUUGCAGGGCCGUUCUCGGGGACUGAUGAUCGAGGCUUGUGCCCAUGCAACCUUCUUCUGCAAACUAUUAUAUAAUUUGAGAGCAUCAUUAAAUAAGAAUCAAAGUUCCAGACAUCUCUCAAUUGGCUCCCUUAAUUCAGCCACUCCUGAAGAGUUUAAGGUGGGCAUCAUUGGAGGUGGCCACCUUGGGAAGCAGCUGGCUGGCACACUGCUGCAGCUUGGCCCCAUCCCUGCUGAAAGCCUGCGGAUCUCCACUCGGAGGCCAGAGACUCUGGGUGAGCUCCAGAAGCUGGGAAUCAAAUGCUUUUACCAUAACGCUGAUCUGGUGAGUUGGGCCGAUGUGAUAUUCCUCUGCUGCUUGCCGUCUCAGCUGCCUAAUAUCUGCGUAGAAAUUUACACCAGCCUUGAGAAGGCCAGCAUUGUGUACAGCUUUGUAGCUGCCAUCCCACUACCCAGGCUGAAACUACUGUUGAACCACACCAAUAUCUUGCGGCCUCAGUAUCAGUAUGAUGAAGAUUCUGUCAGCGUCUGGGGGGCCAAUAAGGGAGUCAUAGCUGCUCUCCAAGAUCCUACGAUUCUUCAAGCUACCUGUCCCUACAGUCCUGCUGGGGGAAUAAUCCUCAAUAUCAAGUGGUUGGAGGGAGUGUUCUAUGCGGCCCUAAACAUAUGCACAGCAAGAAACAUGGCCCACUCCCAAGUGCUGCAGCUUCUGAGUGAACUCUUUCUCUCCGUGCACUUUGAAGACUGUGGGAAAGACACAGCAUCUUGCCCAAAGUUGCAAUUAACAGAUUUUGUCAGCAAAGCCUAUGGCAAGAAUUUGUCUCAGGAAAGGCCUUUCCCCUGGUUUGAUCUGACUGCUGUGCAACUCAAGGAAACUCCGUUUAGCCAGCAUCUCUCAAGUAGUCCUGUUCUCCAAGACCACCUUACCCAUCUAUACUGUGCUUCAUUUGGCAUCUCCCUAACCAAAGAACAGCCAGUCAUUUCCACAGGCUUUCCAUCCCAAUAAGAGAACUCAGGAAUCAGGAUUUUUUCCCACUCACAGAUUUUCCCUAUAAUAGUUGUGCCCUGAUUAUCACAAUUGACUGUGGGAGUCUUGUGGCUGUAUUGUGUUUGCCACAUGAUAGACAUCAGGAAUUAUAAAACUGUACUGAUGACUCUUUAAAAUGUAGAAUAAAACAAGUGGUCCUAUCCAUCAAUAUGUAUCUGGCUCUCAGAAGCAACUAGUGAAACUACACAACCUAACUUAAGUAAGCUGCUCCCGCAGAAAAGUCUUGUUAAUACAAAUUAUUUCUCUUCUAAAAUUAAAGAAGUUAUAAUGUUAUAAGUUUUAGACAAUUACAUACUGCAGCUUCUUUUCCAAUAAAUCAAGUUUCAAUCCAUUUGCCAGCAGUAGGUAGCUGGAAAAAGAUACAGUUUGAUUUUCUCACAAUUUUGGACAGAGAAGUGAAGGUAUGGUAAACCAUCUUAAUUGAAUUAUGGCUUGUAUCAUGCUUAUUUUGACUAUAUAUGACUGUUCUGGUACUAUCUUAUUUACAGCUGUUCCCAUUUAAACCAUUUAAAAAACUGGUAUUUAAUGGCUAAAACUAAUUUUGCAAAAUAUAGAUCUAUACUGCAAA